ACGGAAGCUCUGCCUGUGCGACCGCCGCCCACCCGAGCCUAUCUGGGCUGCGUCUUCUCGCCGCUGCUCUUCGUGGCCCAACGCCCCAAUCCUUGCGUGUGCUUGCAGUCCCACCCCACACUCAGCCUUGUGUCCCUCGAUCCAGUCUCCGACUUCCAUUUCCCACCCUAAACCGCCUACCCGGUGUCUGUUCCCCGCCCGGUUGUCCUCGCCCUGCUGCGCUGAGUGUCCCCUGUUAGCCUCGACCCCAUGGCGCUGCAGACGCUGCAGAGCUCGUGGGUGACCUUCCGCAAGAUCCUGUCUCACUUCCCCGAGGAGCUGAGUCUGGCUUUCGUCUACGGCUCCGGGGUGUACCGCCAGGCAGGGCCGAGUUCAGACCAGAAGAAUGCUAUGCUGGACUUUGUGUUCACAGUAGAUGACCCUGUCGCAUGGCAUUCAAAGAACCUGAAGAAAAAUUGGAGUCACUACUCUUUCCUAAAAGUUUUAGGGCCCAAGAUUAUCACGUCCAUCCAGAAUAACUAUGGCGCUGGAGUUUACUACAAUUCAUUGAUCAUGUGUAAUGGUAGGCUUAUCAAAUAUGGAGUUAUUAGCACUAACGUUCUGAUUGAAGAUCUCCUCAACUGGAAUAACUUAUACAUUGCUGGACGACUCCAAAAACCGGUGAAAAUUAUCUCAGUGAACGAGGAUGUCACUCUUAGAUCAGCCCUCGAUAGAAAUCUGAAGAGUGCUGUGACCGCUGCUUUCCUCAUGCUCCCCGAAAGCUUUUCUGAAGAAGACCUCUUCAUAGAGAUUGCCGGUCUCUCCUAUUCAGGUGACUUUCGGAUGGUGGUUGGAGAAGAUAAAACAAAAGUGUUGAAUAUUGUGAAGCCCAAUAUAGCCCACUUUCGAGAGCUCUAUGGCAGCAUACUACAGGAAAAUCCUCAAGUGGUGUAUAAAAGCCAGCAAGGCUGGCUGGAGAUAGAUAAAAGCCCAGAAGGACAGUUCACUCAGCUGAUGACAUUGCCCAAAACCUUACAGCAACAGAUAAAUCAUAUUAUGGACCCUCCUGGAAAAAACAGAGAUGUGGAAGAAACUUUAUUCCAAGUGGCUCAUGAUCCCGACUGUGGAGAUGUGGUGCGACUAGGGCUUUCAGCAAUCGUGAGACCGUCUAGUAUAAGACAGAGCACGAAAGGCAUUUUUACUGCUGGUAAGAGCUUUGGAAAUCCGUGUGUAACAUACCUGCUGACUGAGUGGCUUCCACACUCUUGGUUACAGUGUAAAGCUUUGUAUCUUUUAGGUGCUUGUGAAAUGCUGAGCUUUGAUGGCCAUAAACUGGGAUAUUGCAGUAAGGUACAAACAGGCAUAACAGCAGCAGAACCUGGUGGUCGAACAAUGUCAGACCAUUGGCAGUGCUGUUGGAAGCUUUACUGCCCUUCUGAAUUUUCUGAGACACUUCCUGUGUGCAGGGUUUUUCCCUCAUAUUGUUUUAUUUAUCAAAGUUACAGAUGCAUAGGAUUGCAAAAACAGCAGCAUCUGUGCUCCCCCUCCUCUUCCCCUUCUCUGAGACAACUGCUUCCAUCUGUCUUAGUGGGUUAUUUUUGUUGUUACUGCCAUUUCUCUAAAUGGUAAGUUUUCGUUGCUCCUUCUCUACGUUUCAACUUUAGGUAUCAUCUAUUGACUUCUCUCUAUGGGAGGUUAGAAGUCAACUCUGGCACCCACCCUCAUCAAAUGUACGCACCCUCCCAUCCCUCUGUCCUCCUAAUAUAGUUGUCUGGUGGUUUUGGCUAAUUAGUUUUCAGUUUGAUGGUAUGGUGAGCCACAGAGUACACCUUUCCUUCCCUGCAUAAUGUUCUUCUCUCAUGGAGAGUGUCUUCGCUGUCCCCUCUAGGGGGUCCCCCAUUUACUGUAUCUCAUGUCUUUCACUUGCUUGGUGCACACUCUCAUUUUGGUGAAGCACAUUUUCCAGUAAUUUCCUGAGAAGGGGAACAUGGAAGGCACAUUUGGAGACCACGUAUGUCUGAAAGUCUUUUUUGUCUGUCUUCACCCAUAGUUAAUACUUAGGCUGGGUAUUGAUUAGAAAUCACUUUCCUUUAAAAUUUUGAGAUCAUUGCUGCAUUUAUCUUUUACUUCUAGGAUUGUUGUCUAUGUCUAAAGCCAAUCUGAUUCUUAAUCCUUUGUGUAUGUUAUUUCUGGAAGCAUGUUAGGUCUUUAUUUUUCCCCAGUGCUCUGAAUUCUCUCAGUGAUGUGCUUUGAUGUGAGUCUGUUUUUAUCUGUUUUAUCUGUUUUACCGGGAAUUCAUUGCCCUUUCUGUUGGGAAACUCAGAAUAUAAGCAUAUAAGAAAAAUGUUUUAAAUUUUUUCUUUAAUUUUGUCCCAUCUGUUUUCUCUGUUCUCUUUCUGGAACUCCUUUUAUUCAGAUAUUGCACCCCCUAGAUUAGUCUUUGGUUUUCUUUCUUUUGUCUUCUAUUUUUUAUCUGUUUUUCUUUUGCUCUGCUUUGGAAGAUUUUCUCGAAUUUCUCAACUUUAGCUUCCAACCCUUCUGUUGAGUGUUUAUAAUUUCCAGGAACUCUCUCUUUUCUUGCUGUUCUCUGAAUGCUCCUGUUUUUUGCAUCCUAUUCUUGUUUUAUGGCCUAAAUAUUUGACAUCUCUUUGGAGGACAAAGUGGCUGUAUCAGUUCAUCGUCCCACAAGCAGAGUAGGAGAAUACUCUUUUCUUCCCAUUUUUUCCAACAUUUGGCAUCAUCAAGUGAUAGACUUUUCUAGUUCAGGCUUUCUUCAUGCAAGCAUCCAUUGAGCAUCUCUCAUGUGCCAGCUGCUCGGGAUACAAAAGUGAACACAACGCUGCGUUAGUCUGUUCUCAUGCUGCUAAUAAAGACAUACCUCAGACUGGGUAAUUUAUAAAGGAAAGAGGUUUAAUUGAUUAGCAGUUCCACAUGGCUGGGGGUGUCUCAGAAUCAUGGCGGAAGGUGAAUGAGGAGCAAAAUCAUGUCUUACAUGGCGGCAGGCAAGAGAGCAUGUGCAGGGGAGCUCCCUUUUAUAGAACCAUCAGAUCUCGUAACACUUAUUCACUAUUAUGAAAACAGCACAGGAAAGACCUGCCUUCGUGAUUCAAUUACCUCCCACCAGGUCCCUCCCACGACGUGGGGAUUAUUACAAUUCAGGGUAAGAUUUGGGUGGGAACACAGAGCCAAACCAUAUCAAAUGCUAUACUGACUUGCAGAGGCGUAUAAUUUAGAAGGGAAAAGAGACAUGCUAACAGAAAUUUGCAAGAGAGGGAGAAAUAGCACAGAGGUAGCCCAAAAAGGGGAGUGAUCUUUCAACCUAAUUCUAAUCCCUGGGUUUGAGAUUGCUGGGGAGCUGGUAUGGUCACACCUCUCAGUGUCUCAUAGCCCAGCUGCUUGGAUACUCCUCUGAGCAUUUGGCCCUCAAGGACCGUGUUGCCCUCCUGAAUCACUGGAAAGAUUCAACAAGGCCAGGCAUGGUGGCUCACACUUAUAAUCCCAGCACUUUGGGAGGCCAGGGCGGGAGGAUUGCUUGGGCUCAAGAGUUCAAGACCAGUCUGGGCAACACAGCAAGACCCUGUCUCUUUAAAAAUAACAAAAAUAGGCCAGAUGCGGUGGCUCACACCUAUAAUCCCAGCACUUUGGGAGGCCAAGGCAGGAGGAUCACUUGAGUCCUGGAGUUUGAGAUCAGCCUGGGCAACAUGGUGGAACCCUGUCUCUAAAAAAAUAGAAAAAAUAGGCUGGAUGUGGUGACUCAUGCCUGUAAUCCUAGUACUUUGGGAGGCCGAGACAGGCAGAUUGCCCGAGCUCAGGGGUUUGAGACCAGCCUGGGCAACAUGGUGAAACCCCGUCUCUACUAAAAUACAAAAAAUUAGCUGGGCGUGGUGGCACAUGCCUGUAGUCCCACCUUUGAGCGGCUGAGGCAGGAGAAUUGCUUGAACCUGGGAGGCGGAAGUUGCAGUGAGCCAAGAUUGUGCCACUGCCUCUGGCCUGGGCGAGAGUGAGACUUCGUCUCAAAAAAAAAAAAAAAAAAAAAAAAAAAAGGGCUGGGCGUGGUGGUGCGCGCCCGUAGUCCUGAGCCCAGGAAGUCGAGGCGGCAUUGAGCUAAGAACGCACCACUGCACUUCAGUCUGGGUGACAGAGUGAGACCCUGUCUCAAAAAAAAAAAAAAUUAUAAUAAUAAAAACAUUGUAUAAAAGUUUCAACAAAGACUUAGUAGCACUUGUGUCACAUCUGCUGAACUAAAGAUUUUCCUACCAUUUGGGUGCAUGGCUUUGCAUUUCCAGUUAAGAUAUUCAUUUAAUCUAUGUUCCUGCUAGUUUACUCUGGCAAGACUGAAGAUGAGGUACUUUUGUUUGUUUGGGUGAUUCAUGCUGUUAAUCUGAAUUUUGCAUGAUUGCCUUUCCCUUGCCAUGAUCCUCCUUGGGUGAGGCUUAAUGAUUUGUUUUGUUGUUGGCGUCCCAUGCUAUAAGGAAUUAUUGGAAUUAUUAGAAUUAUUGUUAAUUAUUUUUCAGUUGUGACAAUGGUGGUGUUAUGGAGCUUUUUAAAAAAUUCCCUUUCUUUUAGAGAUGCAUACUAAAAUAAUUCCAGAUGCAAUGAUAUGUUGUCUGGGAUUUGCUUCAAAAUAAAACAUGGCAGAGGGCAGUGGGUAAUGGGUAGAUGACACAAGAUUGGCCAUGAGCUGAUAUAUUGUCAAAGCUAGGUAAAGAUGCAUGGGGCUGUUUUAUACUCUUCUGUCUGUUAUUUAAGUUUGAAUUUUUCUCUAAUAAAAGGCUGAAAAAGA